AGCCUCGCCGAGUCCUCGGUGCGGGCUGCGAGCGGGACCCGCGGAGCUGCGCUGUCCUCGACGCCUCCGCCAGGCGCGGGCCGAGGAGCCUCCAAGAGCUGGCCCGGCCCCCGGCCGCCGCCGCCCAACCCCGGGCAUCUGCCCCGCGCCGUUGUCCCCGCGGCUUCGGGCCGGCGGGACCGCCCCGUCCCUUCCAGGGGUGACCCGGGGGUCGCGGGUGGGACGGCGCCUGCGGCCGAGUCUGGGGGGCGCCGGGUGUCGGGUCGGGAAGCGGCCGCCGCGACUCUUGCCUCCCGGGCGUCGUUGCUCCACGGGCCUGCCUCCACCCGCGGGGACAGGUGCCCCGGCUGGGGUCUGUUGGGAAGAUGGCGACCCCGGGCAUGAGCUGGCAGCAGCACUAUUACGGCGGCUCGGCGGCCAAAUUCGCGCCCUCGCCGGCCACCGCACAGCUGGCUGGGCACAGCAUGGACUACAGCCAGGAGAUGCACCUGAAAAUGAGCAAGAAAAUCGCCCAGCUCACCAAGGUAAUAUAUGCUUUAAACACUAAAAAUGAUGAGCAUGAAUCUGCAAUUCAAGCCCUCAAAGAUGCUCAUGAAGAAGAAAUUCAACAAAUUCUUGCUGAAACAAGAGAAAAAAUAUUGCAGUAUAAAAGCAAAGUAACAGAGGAGCUAGACCUUAGAAGAAAGAUUCAAGUUUUAGAAUCAUCAUUAGAAGAUCACAUAAAAAUGAAGCAGCAGGCUUUGACAGAAUUUGAAGCUUAUAAGCACAGAGUUGAGGACAUGCAACUUUGUGCAGAAGCCCAGCAUGUCCAACGCAUAGUGACCAUGUCUAGAGAAGUCGAAGAGAUUAGAAGGAAAUUUGAAGAAAAAUUACGGAGCUUUGGACAACUUCAAGUACAGUUUGAAAAAGACAAACGAUUGGCAUUGGAAGACUUGCAAGCUGCUCACAGACGGGAGAUACAAGAGCUAUUGAAGUCACAGCAGGAUCACAGUGCCUCAGUAAAUAAAGGCCAGGAAAAGGCAGAGGAACUACACAGAAUGGAGGUGGAGUCCCUAAACAAAAUGCUUGAGGAGCUAAGACUUGAACGGAAGAAACUAAUUGAGGAUUAUGAAGGCAAGUUGAAUAAAGCUCAGUCCUUUUAUGAACGUGAGCUUGAUACUUUGAAAAGGUCACAGCUUUUUACAGCAGAAAGCCUACAGGCCAGCAAAGAAAAGGAAGCUGAUCUUAGAAAAGAAUUUCAGGGACAAGAAGCAAUUUUACGAAAAACUAUAGGAAAAUUAAAGACAGAGUUACAGAUGGUACAGGAUGAAGCUGGAAGUCUUCUUGACAAAUGCCAAAAGCUUCAGACGGCACUUGCCAUAGCAGAGAACAAUGUUCAGGUUCUUCAAAAACAGCUUGAUGAUGCCAAGGAGGGAGAAAUGGCCCUAUUAAGCAAGCACAAAGAAGUGGAAAGUGAGCUAGCAGCUGCCAGAGAACGUUUACAACAGCAAGCUUCAGAUCUUGUCCUCAAAGCUAGUCAUAUUGGAAUGCUUCAAGCAACUCAAAUGACCCAGGAAGUUACAAUUAAAGAUUUAGAAUCAGAAAAAUCGAGAGUCAAUGAGAGAUUAUCUCAACUUGAAGAGGAAAGAGCUUUUUUGCGAAGCAAAACCCAAAGUCUGGAUGAAGAGCAGAAGCAACAGAUUCUAGAACUGGAGAAGAAAGUAAAUGAAGCAAAGAGAACUCAGCAAGAAUAUUAUGAAAGGGAACUUAAAAACCUGCAAAGUAGAUUGGAAGAGGAGGUGACUCAAUUAAACGAGGCCCAUUCUAAGACUUUGGAAGAAUUAGCUUGGAAGCACCAUAUGGCAAUUGAAGCUGUCCACAGUAAUGCAAUUAGGGAUAAGAAAAAACUGCAAAUGGAUUUGGAAGAACAACAUAACAAAGAUAAACUAAACCUGGAAGAGGAUAAAAAUCAGCUUCAACAAGAGCUAGAAAACCUAAAGGAAGUACUGGAAGACAAGUUGAAUACAGCCAAUCAAGAGAUUGGCCACCUCCAAGAUAUGGUAAGGAAAAGUGAACAAGGUCUUGGCUCUGCAGAAGGACUUAUUGCUAGUCUUCAGGACUCCCAGGAAAGGCUUCAGAAUGAGCUUGACUUGACUAAAGACAGCCUAAAGGAGACCAAGGAUGCUCUAUUAAAUGUGGAGGGUGAGCUAGAACAAGAAAGGCAACAGCAUGAAGAAACAAUUGCUGCCAUGAAAGAAGAAGAGAAGCUCAAAGUGGACAAAAUGGCCCAUGACUUAGAAAUUAAGUGGACUGAAAAUCUUAGACAAGAGUGUUCUAAACUUCGUGAAGAGUUAAGGCUUCAACAUGAAGAGGAUAAGAAGUCAGCAAUGUCUCAACUUUUGCAGUUGAAAGAUCGAGAGAAAAAUGCAGCAAGAGAUUCAUGGCAGAAGAAAGUAGAAGAUCUCUUAAACCAGAUUUCCUUGCUGAAACAGAAUCUGGAGAUACAGCUUUCCCAGUCUCAGACUUCUUUGCAACAACUGCAAGCCCAGUUUACGCAAGAACGACAGCGGCUUACGCAAGAGCUUGAAGAAUUAGAGGAGCAACAUCAGCAAAGACACAAAUCAUUAAAAGAAGCACAUGUCCUUGCAUUUCAAACUAUGGAAGAGGAAAAGGAAAAGGAGCAAAGAGCUCUUGAAAAUCAUUUACAACAGAAGCAUUCUGCAGAGCUUCAAUCACUAAAAGAUGCACACAGAGAGUCAAUGGAGGGCUUCCGGAUAGAAAUGGAACAGGAACUUCAGACUCUUCGGUUUGAAUUAGAAGAUGAAGGAAAGGCUAUGCUUGCUUCCUUGCGCUCAGAACUCAACCAUCAACAUGCAGCUGCAAUUGAUUUGUUACGGCAUAAUCAUCAUCAAGAAUUGGCAGCUGCUAAAAUGGAAUUAGAGAGAAGCAUAGACAUCAGCAGAAGACAGAGUAAGGAGCACAUAUGUAGAAUUACAGAUCUACAAGAGGAAUUAAGACACAGAGAGCAUCACAUCUCUGAAUUGGAUAAGGAGGUUCAGCACCUUCAUGAGAAUAUAAGUGCCCUAACCAAAGAACUGGAAUUUAAGGGGAAAGAAAUUCUCAGAAUACGAAGUGAAUCUAACCAACAGAUAAGGUUGCAUGAACAAGAUUUAAACAAGAGACUUGAAAAAGAGUUGGAUGUCAUGACAGCAGACCACCUCAGAGAGAAAAAUAUCAUGCGGGCAGAUUUUAAUAAGACUAACGAGCUACUCAAGGAAAUAAAUGCCGCUUUACAAGUGUCAUUAGAAGAAAUGGAAGAAAAAUAUCUAAUGAGAGAAUCAAAACCAGAAGAUAUACAGAUGAUUACAGAAUUAAAAGCCAUGCUUACAGAAAGAGACCAGAUCAUAAAGAAACUAAUUGAGGAUAAUAAGUUUUAUCAGCUGGAAUUAGUCAAUCGAGAAACUAACUUCAACAAAGUGUUUAACUCAAGUCCUACUGUUGGUGUUAUUAAUCCAUUGGCUAAGCAAAAGAAGAAGAAUGAUAAAUCACCAACAAACAGGUUUGUGAGUGUUCCCAAUCUAAGUGCUCUGGAAUCUGGUGGAGUGGGCAAUGGACAUCCUAACCGCCUGGAUCCCAUUCCUAAUUCUCCAGUCCACGAUAUUGAGUUCAACAGCAGCAAACCACUUCCACAGCCAGUGCCACCUAAAGGGCCCAAGACAUUUUUGAGUCCUGCUCAGAGUGAAGCUUCUCCAGUGGCUUCUCCAGAUCCCCAGCGCCAGGAGUGGUUUGCCCGGUACUUCACAUUCUGAAAGAAUUGUGUUGGCACAGCUCUGUAUAGACUGUUACUAAGAGCAUGACUUUAUACAGAUUGUUAUGUAAAUAGGCUUUCCUAUGUCAAACACUGUGAAUGAGAAAGUAUUUGUCUCUCCAACUUGAAAAUGCACUGUAUUUCCUGUGAUAUUUAUUGGAAUCAUUCUAUAAGGUACUAUAUUAUGUGUGUAAUUAUAACUGUUAUUUUUAUUUGAGAUGGAAGAGUCUUUAACCUUUGUAAUUACUGCAUAAUAAAUUUUGUUAGAAUCAAACAAUGCUUUUUAUUUUUUUCUACGUUUGCUUUAAUUUUUAAAUAUUUUUUAAUUCCAGGUAAGACUU